AUGGGAGAGAAAGAGGAAGCCCUGGGCAUGUGUGUGCCAGCACUUGUCAGUGUGCACCUAUGUGUGCAUACAAGGCCAGCGGAGAAGACCUUCAAGCAGCGCCGCACCUUCCAACAAAGAGUAGAUGUCCGACUUAUUCAAGAGCAGCAUCCAGCCAAAAGCCCGGUGAUAACAGAACGAUACCAAGGUGAGAAGCAGCUUCCUGUCCUGGAUAAAACGAAGUUCCUUGUACCUGACGUUCGAGACGUCAACAUGAGUGAGCUCAUCAAGAUAAUUAGAAGGCGCUUACAGCUCAAUGCUAAUCAAGCCUUCCUCCUGGUGGUGAACGGACAUAGCAUGGUGAGCGUCUCCACACCAGUCUCAGAGGUGUAUGAGAGUGAGAAGGAUGAAGAUGGAUUCCUAUACAUGGUCUAUGCCUCCCAGGAGACGUAUGGGAUGAAAUUGUCAGUGUAA